CUCCAGGAAAAAACAAAAACAAAAACAAAAACAAAAAACAAACCAGCACUCUUCACUUGACUCCUGGGACCCUGGCUCCCCACACAGACUGCCUUGGUGCCAUCUUUAUAUAUAGUGUUUAGAACCUUCACCUUCUCUUGCUGCAUGAUUUGAUAAUAUCUUUCUGAUGGGCAAGGAGGAAGACGGAAGGUUUUGGGGUGUAUGUCAUUGUGGUUGCCAAGAACAAGUUGUCAUAGUAACAUAUCUUUCCUUCCUUGUGAAACAUUCCAAAGAGGUUUUUUCCCCCUUUGGCUUUCCUCUGACUCUGGGGAAAAUACAUCCCAUCCCCUGCAGAGGAGUGCAGAAGCAGGCAGUCAGACAGACACAAAGGGUGGGGAGUAAUUGGGCGAGAUGUGCAAAAGUCAACUCAAUUCCUAAUAUCAAGCAAUUAGGCUAAUGUGAUUUAGAACAACGUGAUCAGUGAAGUUUGUGUUUAUGCUCCCCUCAGACUGUAAUUAAUUCAUGGAAGUGCUGUAGGUUGUUAAAUUUUGUAAACGGAUAAUAGAACUGUUCUUUGAAAUAAAAGCAGUGGCAACAACCUAGUCAUUUUACAGUAGCGUGAAUAGAAGAUAAUUACAGUUUGAGAGAACAUAGCCCCCUUUCCGUACAAGAACAGGAAUGGAUUGUCUUCGGCUGGGAGUUGCUGUGAGCACAAAUUGCAAACAAAGUUUAUGUGCUCUGCGGGGAAAUGGCAGGCAUUUUCCCCAUAUAGUCAAGGAGAGUGCCUAACUCACUUUUUAGAUAUUUCUACCAGUGUCCUACAGGGAAUUGUGCUAAUAAAUAUGACAAUAACAUUGUAAUGGGACCAGAAAGGCUGACCCAGCGUUUUGUUAAUUUGUGUUCAGCAUUUGCUGGGAGCUUUGUAACCCCUGAGCAAUGAAACAGGAGCAUAUUGGUUGGACUGUAGGCAUUUUAAUUAGAGGUCCUGGGAAUAACUCUGUGCUGUGGCAGCUGGAUAAGACCUGGCCCCUCAAAGUUUACCCAUGGCGAGCUUCCCUCCUGGCCCUCAGCGGCCAUUAAAAGGUCUUGCUAGAGGAAGGGACCUGGGGGAGGGAGUGCAAAAUUUCUAAGGAGAGGAGGAAGAUGCCUGGUGGGCUGGCGUCCAACAGCAAUUAGCUACUCAGCUGUCAGUGCCCAGAGCCCUUGCUUUAACAAAGUGGUGGCAAAGAUUGACAGAAAUGGCUUGACCCCAUGAUGGAUCCCAAAGCAUUUUGUAAAAGGGUCUUUUUACUCUUGCUACCUUUUCAUCAUCUGGCUUAAAUACAAUGCAACAAUAAAGGCAUCAUAAAUCAAAAGCUGUUAGCACACAUGGCCCCUGCAAUUUAUGGGUAUUAAGCCAAAAAAAAAAAAAAAAAGCUUAGGAACAUUUCAUCAAAUUAUUUUUCCAGUCCCUUAAGACUCAUUUAAAUUUCCCUCCUCUCCCUACCCUGGUGCUGCCAGCUAUUUCAUGCACAGGAGCACCUGAGCCCAGGGUGGAGGGAGCCAACUCUGCCAGCGGGCAGGCGGUUCAUUCUCAUGGGGUGGGGCCUGAAGCUCUGCCCAGCUGCAGGCACCAUGUGGGCAAACAGCCAAGAAUCUAGAGAAACAGAUGGCAGCUGCCCUUGGGUCAGUGAUGCAGCUUUGGGAAUGGCCAUGUCCAUCCACACUAAACCUCCAUCCUCACCUCUUUCACCAUGAGUCCUGGGGCUGGGGUGGGAGCUCCAGUGGGAGAUGGCGGGAUUAUUUGGAGGUAAGGGGCCCAAUGCAAGGUUGGGUUGGGGACUAAAUACUCAAAGCCAGCCACUUCUGUGAUGGUCCAGUGCCGGCUUUGGAGGCCCAAUGCUAAGUCCUGGAAGGCCCGGUGCAGAGUAGUGGGCCCACCAGAGGCCAGCAUUAAGGAGCAGAAUCCCCACUAUGCUCUGGGUAGUGGCUGAUAGAUCUCAACAUGUCAGUGGAGAAGUAGAAACCGGUUGGUGGCGUUACUUAUAUUUGUUAAUUAGUGAGCCCGACACAUAAUUAUUAAGCAUCGAGGAUAGGCAGGGCACAUGGAACAAUUCACCCCGAUGUGCAGAGACACAAAGUCAGAUGAAUGUCCAAAGGGCCAGAAGUGGGCUUCCUGCCCUUCAAGGAUCACCUCCUCCAGGAAGCCUGUACAGGUUGCUAUGAGGAGCAGAUGAGCAUGUGCUGAACAUUCUGAAUACAAUAUGGAUUGUCAGGCUGAGCCCUUGCUCAUUGUUUAUUGGGGGGGGGGAAAUCUCUGUUUUGAUUGUCCUUGAGUUGAGAAGGGACUCUUAAGUUGGAAGCUUUCUGGACCUUUGUUGUGUGGGAAAAGUAGAAGGCAGUUGGCACAGGUGCCUCUGUGGCAUCACCUGGCCCCGUGGUAAAUCCUAUCUUAUUCAAUGAGGAAACAAGGGAAGAGAAGUGGUGUCUCCUUAGCCACUUCUCUGAGCUUGAUGGGAAUAUAUGGCUUAAGAACUCAUAACCGUGGCCUCCAUGACAAUCCCUUGGCUCCCAGGCUCUGUGACUCCCCAGUCCAUCCUGGCUCUCUUCAGAGCACCUCUUCUGCCUGUGAGCGAUUUGUCACCUCAUUCUGUAAGACUGGCACCAGCAGAAAUGCAGUCUCAAAGGAUCCCGGGGAGAAAGCGAGGCCGACCCUCACUUCACUCCACGCCUAUGAAGAUGGCAGUUCAUAACCUUUAUUCUGCUUCAGCUGGCUCUUUACCAGCAGUGAAGAUCCCAAAGAAAAGAGGGCGGAAACCCGGGUACAAGAUCAAGUCUCGGGUUCUCAUGACUCCCUUAGCCCUCUCACCUCCGCGGAGUACCCCAGAGCCCGACCUCAGCUCCAUCCCUCAGGACGCAGCCACGGUCCCCAGCUUGGCGGCCCCACAGGCUCUCACAGUCUGCCUCUACAUCAACAAGCAGGCCAAUGCGGGGCCCUAUCUGGAGAGGAAGAAGGUGCAGCAGCUCCCGGAGCAUUUUGGGCCCGAGCGGCCAUCGGCGGUGCUGCAGCAGGCCGUCCAAGCCUGCAUCGACUGCGCCCACCAGCAGAAGCUGGUCUUCUCCCUGGUCAAGCAGGGCUAUGGUGGUGAGAUGGUGUCAGUCUCGGCUUCCUUUGAUGGCAAACAGCACCUGCGGAGCCUGCCUGUGGUGAACAGCAUCGGCUAUGUCCUCCGCUUCCUCGCCAAGCUGUGCCGAAGCCUCCUGUGCGAUGACCUCUUCAGCCACCAGCCCUUCCCCAGGGGCUGCAGUGCCUCUGAGAAAGUCCAGGAGAAAGAGGAAGGGAGGAUGGAAUCAGUCAAGACAGUCACCACCGAAGAGUACCUGGUGAACCCUGUGGGCAUGAACCGCUACAGCGUGGACACCUCCGCCUCCACCUUUAACCACAGGGGCUCCUUGCACCCCUCCUCCUCGCUGUACUGCAAGAGGCAGAACUCUGGAGACAGCCACCUUGGGGGUGGUCCUGCUGCCACCGCUGGUGGUCCCCGCACUAGCCCCAUGUCUUCUGGUGGCCCCUCGGCACCUGGGCUGAGGCCUCCAGCCUCCAGCCCCAAGAGAAACACGACCUCUCUUGAAGGAAACAGAUGUGCCUCAAGCCCUUCUCAGGAUGCGCAGGAUGCCAGGCGGCCACGGAGCAGGAACCCCUCCGCCUGGACUGUGGAGGACGUGGUGUGGUUUGUGAAGGACGCCGACCCACAGGCUCUGGGGCCUCACGUGGAGCUCUUCAGAAAGCACGAGAUUGAUGGCAACGCUCUGCUGUUGCUGAAGAGUGACAUGGUCAUGAAGUACCUGGGCCUGAAGCUGGGACCUGCACUGAAACUCUGCUACCACAUUGACAAACUGAAGCAAGCCAAGUUCUGACUUUUUUAAAAAGACAGAAGCGAAACCCAAAACAACAGAUCCCAAGAUUAUCUUCUGCCUUACCAAUAUCCCGCCAACAUCACAAACUAGACUCUCCUCUUAAAAUUAACAGCCACAGAGACGUGGUCUUUUUAUAAAACUUGUGAAUCUUUGCCUUUUGAAGAAUUUAACAUGGACCUUUUCGAGAGGCUCCUCUGUGUUCAUAAUUUGCCAAAAAAUUACAAAAGCCUGUGAUUUUUAACAUCCCUGUUAUGCUGGUUUCUCUUAAAGUGGGUCCUAUUUGCAUAACGAGAGAGUGGGGAACUGAAUGCUUAUGCCCAAGGAGAGUUCUGGAGGGUUCAAAGGAUGAAAGAAGGACCUUUGUCCCUGCGGUCUCUGCAGGGACAACCCCCUCAGCACCAUCUGCCUCUAACUCUGACCUGGGGACCUAUCCAUGUGAGCCUUGUUUGCCUCAGCUCUGGAAGCUGACUUCUGAAGAUGACUGCCUCACCUUGCACUGUCUGGAAAACUUGAAUUAUUUUACGCCGUGAAAGAAAAAGGAAAAAAAAAAAAAUCUUUUCUGUUCCUAGAAAAUCUGAAGUACUGUGUUUCUCCGCUAGAGGGCAGACUGCUAAUGAAAUUUCAGGACCCUCACUGACUGCAGUAGCAGGAUUGUUCAGUACUGAGUGGAUGGGUUAGGGUGUCUGUGAACAAGAUCUAGCCCACACAGAAACAGGGGAUUUAUUCCACAGUUAGCACCACAGAUUGCGACUUGGGAAGAAACCAUCAGCUAGAGGGGUCUAGUUCGUAUCCAAUCAUUAUUGACUGACUGACUGAUACUCAACUAGCAAAGGCAAGAAUUUGGAAGCACGCUCUACCCAGAUGGGACUUUGGAGUUCCUUCCCUUCCAGAGUCCUUAUUGAGGUGUUGAAGUGUUGGCAUGCCGAAGAAUCUUAGUGACAUUUAGCCAUGGGUGUUUCUUUAAAAAAGGAAAAGAAAAUGUCUCAACGAAGCUUUGAAAUGGGAGAGUGUUGAUUUCUAGUUACAUUGCUGGGUUAUGUAGUUGUAUCUGUGGCUAAUUUUUCUAGUCCUCAACAAAUACACAGACAUGCUAUUAUGGGGUUUAAUUCAAUUUACAAAUAGGUUUUCCUUCCUCACAGUGGAGUAAUAGAAAAAAUUGAUUUUCUGCUCCUUUGCAGCUGUGUCCAGAGACGGACAAUGAAUCCACAAUUUAUUAGGCAGAGGCACAACUUCUCCACCAUUCGUUUUAUCCUUCUCUUUUCUCUGUUUCCCUCCACCUCUCUUCUUCUUCUUUCACACUGAGCAGAAAACAUAUCUUCAAAAUGAAUUCGCCUUUGCCAUGUGCAUAUUCUCUUCCUUAAAAGGACAUCAACAGUGUUGGAGAUGAGGAGAUGAACAUUAGAUUUUGGAAUUUCUGGGAGGGAGAGGGUUAGGGAUGACUCAGGGCCUCCCUUCGCCCAAAGGUGAAUCAGAAAAGGCACCCCUUUCUCUGGGAUACAACCUGAGCAGGGGUCUCAGCUGGCAAGUGGAGCAGGGUGGGGGCUCAACCUCCUCACCGCUUGAUCAGCUGCCGUUGUACAGAGCAUGACCUGUAUAACCUUGAGGGCAGCCCUGGGUAGAUCUGCAGAGUGACCCUCUAUAUAGUUAGAAUCCAGAUGAAGGCCAUAAGAAAUAGUCCAUGCCAUGCCGUUAGGCCCACUUUCAUGUGCAGUACUUGAGAAAGCACAUCGUAGCCUCCUUUUCAGACACACAAAUGGCGGCUGGACUGAGAGCAUGGCAGAGAAGGGGAGGAGGAGAAUGUACUAAACUUGCUCACUGAAUUGAGCUUGAGUUAUUAGAUUGUAGAAGAGCUUGAUGUCUGGUGAUUUUGUUACAGGAAGGGGGUCCCGAUCCAGACCCCAAGAGAGGGCUCUUGGAUCUCAUGCAAGAAAGAAUUCAGGGUGAGUCCAUAAAGUAAAGUGAAAGCAAGUUUAUUAAGAAAGUAAAGGAAGGAAAGAAUGGCUACCCCAUAGUCAAAGCAGCUCUGAGGGCUGCUGGUUGCCCAUUUUUAUGUUUAUUUCUUGAUAUGCUAAACAAGGGGUGGAUUAUUCAUGCCUCCCCCUUUUAGAUCAUAUAGGGUAACUUCCUGAUGUUGCCAUGGCAUUUGUAAACCGUCAUGGCACUGGUGGUAGUAUAGCAGCGAGGACAACCAGAGGUCACUCUCGUUGCCAUCUUGGUUUUGGUGGGUUUUAGCCAACUUCUUUACUGCAACCUGUUUUAUCAGAAGGUCUUUAUGACCUAUAUCUUGUGCUGACCUCCUGUCUCAUCCUGUGACUCAGAAUGCUUUAGCCAUCUGGGAAUGCAGCCCAGUAGGUCUCAGCCUCAUUUUACCCAGCUCCCAUUCAAGAUGGAGUUGCUCUGGUUCAAAUGCCUCUGACAGGUUCAGCACCUGAGAAAAGUACCUUGAAUCAGGCCUUGGGGCAGAGUCUUCAAGAUUUUAAGGUGAUAGGGCCUGUCUCUUAAGAAUUUAUUAAUCGUAAGUGCUCACUGCUGGUUUAGAGUUAGAUACAUUUCCCUCAAAACAGCCAUGGGCAGGUUAUGUACUCAGAACUGCCAGGGUGAAAACAAUGAGAUCCAGAAAAAUCCCACAACAAUCCAGGUUUUUCACUCCUCUUUUUUUUCUCAAUCUUCCGAUACUUGUGGUACCUCUUCCAUCAACAGAUACCUCAUGUAGUGACUUCCAGUAUCAAGUUUUCAAAACUUCCUACCCACCCUCAUCAGUGCCUCCUUCACUACAGAGUCACAAACAUUGGUGCUCUCAAAUAAAAAUCAGCCCCAAACAAUGUCAAAGAGAUCCCUUGAGUAGUUUUCAGGCGAGAGAUAUGUUCUCAUUUCAAGUCUUGGAGAAAACUGGAUCCAUGUUCACGUGGAACUUCUCUCGCGGAGGUGCUAUCUCAUUUUGCAUUAAACUUUAAGCAGGACAGAUUGCUGAAGCCAUGAUAUUUAAGGUUUGACUUUUUAAAAAUCUCAUUACUCUUAAAAUAAAUGCUGCCACAUCAGAGAAUAA